GCGCGCUGCGGGCACCUCUCGGACAAGGCCCCAGCCGUCGCGGGUUGCCGGGCAGAGUCGGACGCCGCCAGCUCUUCACUCCACGCCCACCUCUCUCCUGGAGCGCUGGGCCUUCGCUGGCCGCACCGGCAGCCAUGAGCUCGGAGAUGGAGCCGCUGCUCCUGGCCUGGAGCUAUUUUAGGCGCAGGAAGUUCCAGCUCUGCGCCGAUCUAUGCACGCAGAUGCUGGAGAAGUCCCCUUAUGACCAGGCAGCUUGGAUCUUAAAAGCAAGAGCGCUAACAGAAAUGGUAUACAUAGAUGAAAUUGAUGUAGAUCAGGAAGGAAUUGCAGAAAUGAUGCUGGAUGAAAAUGCUAUAGCUCAAGUUCCACGCCCUGGAACGUCUUUGAAACUCCCUGGAACUAAUCAGACAGGAGGGCCUAGCCAGGCCGUUAGGCCAAUCACACAAGCUGGAAGACCCAUUACAGGUUUCCUCAGGCCCAGCACGCAGAGUGGAAGGCCAGGCACUAUGGAACAGGCUAUCAGAACACCCAGAACCGCCUACACAGCCCGCCCUAUCACCAGCUCCUCCGGAAGAUUUGUCAGGCUGGGAACGGCUUCCAUGCUUACAAGUCCUGAUGGACCAUUUAUAAAUUUAUCUAGGCUGAAUUUAACAAAGUAUUCCCAGAAACCUAAGUUGGCAAAGGCUUUGUUUGAGUAUAUCUUUCAUCAUGAAAAUGAUGUUAAGACUAUUCAUCUUGAAGAUGUAGUUCUACAUCUUGGAAUUUACCCAUUCUUAUUGAGGAAUAAAAAUCACAUUGAAAAAAAUGCUUUGGAUCUGGCUGCCCUCUCCACAGAACAUUCUCAGUACAAGGACUGGUGGUGGAAAGUACAGAUUGGAAAAUGUUACUACAGGUUGGGAAUGUAUCGUGAAGCAGAAAAACAGUUUAAAUCAGCCCUGAAGCAGCAGGAAAUGGUAGAUACAUUUCUGUACUUGGCAAAAGUUUAUGUCUCAUUGGAUCAACCUGUGACUGCUUUAAAUCUUUUCAAACAAGGCUUAGAUAAGUUUCCAGGAGAAGUAACCCUGCUCUGUGGAAUUGCAAGAAUCUAUGAGGAAAUGAACAAUAUGUCAUCAGCAGCAGAAUAUUACAAAGAAGUUUUGAAACAAGACAAUACUCAUGUGGAAGCCAUCGCAUGCAUUGGAAGCAACCACUUCUAUUCUGAUCAGCCAGAAAUAGCUCUCCGGUUUUACAGGCGGCUGCUGCAGAUGGGCAUUUAUAACGGCCAGCUUUUUAACAAUCUGGGGCUGUGUUGCUUCUAUGCCCAGCAGUAUGAUAUGACUCUGACCUCAUUUGAACGUGCCCUUUCUUUGGCUGAAAAUGAAGAAGAGGCAGCUGAUGUCUGGUACAACUUGGGACAUGUAGCUGUGGGAAUAGGAGAUACAAAUUUGGCCCAUCAGUGCUUCAGGCUGGCUCUGGUCAACAACAACAACCACGCCGAGGCCUACAACAACCUGGCUGUGCUGGAGAUGCGGAAGGGCCACGUUGAACAGAUUGGAGAUCUGCAGAGAAGCUAUGUUGCUGCGCAGAAGUCUGAAGCAGCAUUUCCAGACCAUGUGGACACACAACAUUUAAUUAAACAAUUAAGGCAGCAUUUUGCUAUGCUCUGAUUGUUCCUUAGACCACAUAUGUUCUUAUGAAGCAGCAUUAUGCAAGGGGAAAAAAGCACUAUGUCUGUGUAUGUAUGUAUAUAGUGUAAUACGUAUAUUUUAACAAACCUGUCCUUGAUAUUAGUUAAGGUGACACAUAAGGGUGACACAGAAUGUGUAAUGCAAAUUUCAUAGUAAUAGUAACUUUAUAAAAUAAUAUUAUAAAAUACAGGAUUUAAACCUUUCUAAAUAGAUCCUGAAACUGUCUCUCACAUUAUAUAGUAGAUGUUUGUUUAUAAUGUUUACAAAACAUUUUGGUGAAUUUCCUCAAUGUUUUAUAAAUGUACAUUUUUUAAGUCCUUAAGCUGACUCUUAGCCAUCAUGUAGCUUAAGGAGUCUGAAAUCUGCCAUUAAAACUGCACCUUUAAGCCAGGUGUGGUAGCAUGUGCCUAUAGUCCCAGCUACUUGGGAGGUGGAGGUGGGAGGAUUAUAAAUAGAGACUUUCCUUAAGACUUUAAAAAUGUAUUUAAAACUAUUUUUUAUUAAAUACUUUGUGAUUUCCUAUUAAGCUUUAAAAUAAAUCAUUGUGUAAAACACCAUCAUUUCAUUAUUUUUUAAUGAGUUUUUAUUUUAGUCAUCUCAGGUGAAACAGGUUUUACAGAAGUCCAGUAAUCUUAGAAAUCAUCAUUAUUUUAAUUUUAUUUCAAAUGAUAUACCACCAAUUCUGUUUUUUCCUAAAAAGUGAUUUAUGGGAUGUCACAUUAUUAAUAAUAAGAAUAUUCAGAUUAGAAAUAGAGUCACAGGCCAGGAGUCCCACUUCUGGUCAGCCACAGCACGGAAGUCAGCAAUAUUCCAGUACCAUGCAUGGCAUAGCAGCCUUAGAAAGGCUCUUGAACUUUUCUCUGCCUUAUUUAGUGGAACUCUUAUUAAAGUGUUCACACAAGGAAAUGUGUUAAUGGGACAGGACCACUCAAACUCAUACUUUGGACUUUGGGACCUCCAUGUUAUUUUUCAUUUUUUUAACUUCAUGAAAACUAUUUGAUAGAUACUUCUAUUCUUUUCAGAUUUGUAUAAAUUGUAUACUCAGCUGAGAGAACAAAAAAAUUGAAUUCAAGGAAUGAUAGCUUGCUCAAGGCUAGCAUUCACUACAGACAAGAAAGCAAGGCCCCGCGUCACAUCCAUAGCUGCAGCCCAAGGUCUUGUUCCUGCACCUUAGACUUGAACCUUUCUUGGUUCUCUGUGAUGUGUUAGUGUUUAUUUAGCCCUUGAGAAUUUCCUCAGGUACUAUCACAUUUCCUAAUAUCGUAGUCAAUAUUUAGAUUCAAAUGGUAUAAUGUGAAUCAUUUUCUUAAUUUAAAAUAAGAGCUAAUAAGAAUGGCUGAACAUUUACUGAGGAUGUUAAAUAUGCCCACUGUUCUGAGCUCUUUAUGGGAAUGAAUUCAUUUCAUUCUCACCGUAGUCCUAUGCAGGCUGUUAUUCCAUUUUACUUAUGAGAAUACUGAGGCAUAGUAAAAAGCUUAUUGAACUAGUAGUAAGUGCCAAAGAUUCAGGUUUAGGCAGCGUGGCCUCUUGAGUGUGUGCUCUUAAUCACUAGGUCAAAUCACCUCUCUCUGUUUCUGCUGUAAAUAAAUCUACUACCAUUUAAAAUGAACAUUGUGUGCAUUAGGAAAGUUGAAUAAUAAGGGAAUAUUAACACAGCAAAAAAUAAAUGAUUCCAUUUUCCUAAGGUGAUAUGGAGGGAUUUUGUCUUGAAUUUAUGUGAAUUCAGUGUGAGCAUGAAGGCAAAGAAUGAGUCACAGUGGCUCAGGGCAGAAUGAUGACAUAGCACCGUGGAUGACUGUAUCAGAAGCGACAUUCAGGAUGUCUUUGUAACAACAUUUCCUAUGGACUGCGUAACUUCUGGCUUCUGUGCCAACAUUUCUGUAGAAAGAACACAAAAAAUACUAAUAAUUGUUUUCCAGUUUUCCACUGUGGCUAAAGAGGUGCUCAAUCCAUAAAUACAAAUUGCUCAACCAAAAUUCAUAUCAUCGAGCAUAUUUCCAACUGAUGAAAAUGAGAUCUGGCAAGAAGGCUUCCUGCGCUAAAACAUUACUGAGGUUAGAAGUUCUUCCUUUUUUACAAAUGUGUCAUGGCUGAGCCAGUCCCCAUAGUGAUAACUCUUCCAUUGCAUUUCUGAGUGCUUUUUCCCAGGCUCAGAUUAUCUAUCAGGAUACAAUUUAUGGCCUACAGAUAAGAAAAUUAAUAAAGGUAACGUGUCACUACAUUAUUAUUAUUAUUAUUAUUAUUAUUAUUAUUAUUAUUAUUAUUAUGACAGUCUUGCUCGGUCGCCCAGGCUGAAGUGCAGUGGCAUGAUCUUGGCUUACUGCAACCUCUGCCUCCCGGGUUCAAGCAAUUUUCGUGCCUCAGCCUCCCAAGCAGCUGGGAUUACAGGCAUGCACCACCACACCCAGCUAAUUUUUGUAUUUUUAGUAGAGACAGGGUUUCACCAUGUUGCUCAGGCUGGUCUCAAACUCCUGGCCUCAAGUGGUCCACCCGCCAUGGCCUCCCAAAGUGCUAAGAUUACAGGUGUGAGCCACUGCACCCAGCGUCUCUACACUUUUAGUUUCCACCACCAACCCUUUACUACAAUGAGGGAUUUCUGUCAGGGUCUUUCAGCUGGGAUUGAAUUUAAGCAUUCAGAAAACAAAUAUUUUAGAAAGGCUGGCAGGACUAAACCUUAGAAAAUAACCCAGAAAUCAAGUGUAGGAAAAAAAGCCAUCACCAAAUAAUUUUGUAUUCUAGGAAAUAGAGAAAUUGGAAUGUUCCAUGUUUAUGUUCCUUGCAGAGUUCCAAAAUGGUCAUCUAGGCUCAGAUUUGAGGGGGAAACAUUUAUUUAGCAAUUUGAAAAUAACUGCACUUUCAUAUCUAUCCAUAUAGAUGGCAUUCGUCCUAUUUUUAGCUAAAUAAAAACAACAUUUUUGAGAGAGACUAUUAUUUCACUUCUUUGAUGUCAAAGCCAGUCCUUGAAAUGAAAGAAUAGACAUGUUGUUAUAAUCCUUGGGAACUAUGUUUCUUGCAAUGUGAUCCUUUUCUUUACCUGAAUCUAAUUCUGACUAAUAAGGGAAAGUGGAUUGUUAAGUGAAAACAACGGGAACUCUUGGUGAAAGCAACCGUGUUAUCUUGGAGAAGAGGCUAGACCUAAACAGAUUUUAGGAAGAAUUUUGUUUUCUUUUUAAAUCAGAAAGAGAGACCCUCUUCCAAUAUUUGAAACUCAAGUUUUUAUGGACUCCAGCACCUUGCAACUGUCACCGCCCCCAAACCCCACCCCUCUUCUGGUCUAAUAGCUUCAAUUUAUUUCUCUCUACUGGAUUAUGUCUUUUUUAAAAAUCACAUUUCCUUUAAGCCUGCCUCCCUUUUUAAAAAUAGACAAUAUAACUGUUUAUUAAAAUAAAGGAAGAGAAAGAAAAUAACCUGAAAAGGAAACUCAUAAAAGAAAUUAAAAUGGUUGAUAAACAUAUGUAACAAAAAAAAUUUGAUAACAGAAUGAAAUUAAUUCAAGAGAAAGAUACAUUUUUAACCUCUUCAGAGAACAAAGAUUUGAAAUGUUUAUUAUAUAUGAGGUGAAGGUACUGUCAAAAUUCACUGUUGGGCAUAUAUAUCAUUACAAUCUUGAGAGUAGUGUGGCAAAUUUUAUUAAAUUCCUUCCAUUUC